ACCAACCUUGGGGAUGGCUUGGGCAUCAUGGCGUCUGCGGUCCUUGCACACUGAGCCUCAGCGUGGACGGGGAGUCUGUCCCAUAGCCUUGUUGGAGGCGGGAAGGAUUCUGGGAUGGCCGAAGGGGUUGGUAACCUUUGGCCCAAGGGUUCAUCAAGGUGUCACAUGUGGCCCACUUGCUCCGACACUGUCCCUCUCUGGGAACCUGUUUUUCCUUUUUCUCGUCCCCUCUCCCCUCCCAUUCCUCAUCACCCUUUCUUCCCGUCUCCUCCCUCAGGUUAAACCUGGAACGAGACCAGGCCCUUCAGGCUCCCAGGAAGUCACAAGGUGUCUCCAGCAGAUGUGCUUCAUCCAAAUCCUCAGCAUGAACACAGCUUGUCCCACACCCAAAUCCUCAAGAUGUUCAGGGGGCUCUGUAGUGUGUUCCCCAACCCUGUGCCCUAGUGACUCUUUGCGCUUGCACGUGGUGUCAUUUAUUAUGCAGGUGUACUUUGUCAAGGGAGCCCCUCUGCUCACAGCACAGGGAAACCAGCCUCCUGGCUAUCUCCUGUCCCUUGUUAAUCUGCAAGACAAAUGGGUGUUGUCAUUAGGCCUUGUCACUGUGAAGGGAAGGGAGAGUAUCACCAUUCCAGCUUGGCAUUUUUGUCCCCCCUACCACCCCGCCCCCCGCCCACUCAUCUUGGCCACAUGGCCUCCAUUUCCGCUCCUGCUUUGUUUCCUCAGCUGGCUCCUGCCCAGACUUCCUGUGGACCACAUGGUCAGAGGAGGCUUCCUGGGAGAGGCGGACUUGGACCAGCCUUGGGGAAUGGCUUGGGUGUCAUGGCAUCUGCUGUCCUUGCACAUCGAGCCUCAUGGUGGACUAGGGAGUCUGUCCCAUGGCCUCAUUGGAGGUGGGAAGGAUUCCGAAGGAAGGAUUCCCCUCAGGGGGAAGGUUCUGAAAGCAAGAAGCUGACAGCAAUUAUCUGAAGAGGUUACAAUGGAUAGCAAUAGUUCCUUGAGGCCACAGACACUCCCAUCUGGAACUUUCCUUCCACAUCCCAACCACCAGCUUCAGGGGUGGCCCGAGCUCUGGAGGAAGGAGAGGCUGCAGCUGUUUCCCACUCCAGGCCAAACCGAGCCUUGAGAUCCUUCUGACUUGAAAGCAGAGCUGAACACCCUGCCACUGUGUUGUCUUCAAACCAAAGUUGUUGCUUAUAAGGACCCCUUGCCUGCAUUUAGCUCUUACAGCAUUGAACAAACUUCCUCACAGUAACCUGGCAAGGAGGGCAGAGCCUAUGUUACGAUCCCAUUUGAGAGAGCAGAGGUGAGGCCCAGGACUUGAGACAGAUCCCUUGGCUGGUACUGCCUGCCCAGGAGAUGACACAGAAUGCAGGGUCUCCCAUGCCUGUGAGUUUGGAUGGUGUUGAUUAGGCCACAUCCGAGACCUGGCUGCAUAGGAGCCUCUCCAAAUUUCCUCAUGGGAUUUGUGAGGCAAGUCUGGCGACAGCAGCAUUCUCCCUGAUGUCUUAGAUUCUCAUGUGAGUCCACAGGGCUCAGGCAAGCAUUAGACAGACUGGGAGAGGUGACUCAAGGUGUUCUUUCAAAGCAGAGGAAACAGAUUUUGUCAUCAGGGAAUAAGCUCCCACCAGGCCACCACACCCAUUGGUCUGCGUGGUGACUCCUGACACUGGCUCCGAGGUAGGGUUCCCGGGCAGUAGGGGCUGGGGAGGGGGAAGGCCUGCUUCCCAUUGUAGCCCUCCCCAGAUGCUGAGUUGCAGCUAGUUCAGCUAAUUGGCAAGAAAAGGAGAAGCAAAAAUAGUGAAAAUCUGCGAAUUAAUAAAACAGCCUUGAAGCAACCGCCAAAAUGUGUACAAAUCAUGAAGUAAUUAGAAGUGUGAAGAAUUCUAUCGGGUUCGCUGUUUCCAAAUCCAACAUCUGAUCGCUUUAGGAGGCCAAGGGCUGGCAGGCCACAGGGAGUAGAAAUUCUUUCCAUUGCCGUCUGAUCUCGCCUCCCUGGGGCCUGGGUUCCCUUGAAAUCCUUGCAGGGUCCUGGAAGUUUCCAUGGGACUUGCUAGAAUCAAAUGUUGGCCUUUUGGGGGCCCGUUAAGCACACGCAACGCCUUAUCCAAGUAGCAUGUAAUAUUUUAGAAUAAUGCUGUUAAGAUUUCGCAAAGUGUUUUUUGGAUCCAUGUUCUUAUUUAAUCUCUCACUAUCACCAAAUAUUUUUAUGUCAGUGUUUUUCAGAGGAGGGAAGCAAGGCCCAGAGAGUGAAGUGGUGUCAACUCAAUUUUAAGAGCCCAUCAGGAGCAGAACUAGGGCUAGAGCCAGGAUCUUCUGAUAGCCCCUCCGACCUCUCCUCUCCCACCCACAUUCCUCCUGUGGGCUCUGCUGCAUCACUCAAUGGUGCCAGGCAUUUGUCUAUCACAAUUGUCUCAGCUAACAGCCAACUACUGUUCUCUCUGGCCAUGGUUUAUUACAUUUAGGGAAGGAGACUUGGUCUGAAAGAUGCCACAUUCCUGCAGCCUCUCUUGGUGCAGUGGAAUACAGUCUUGGGCGAGGUGGCGUGGAUGAGCUGGUGAAAGAGGAUGCUGCCCACAUCCAAAGGCUCCAGAGGAUCCUGGCCUGGCAGCUGAGCUCCCCUGCAUUUGGAACCUCAGGCGUAACUUGGUGUAGAGCUCAUGAAAGGUGCUUGUGUUUCUCCAGCUUUUUUCACCAGUGCUUACCAGACUGGCUCAGGUUUUGGAAUCUAAGGUGAGCUGGUAGAAACAGGAGAGGUAGAAAGAAGCCCCUGGAUGCCUCCAGAAUUCAUUGAUGGGAUCCCUGCAUACUGCUUGGAACACAGAAAGAGGCUGUGACACAGCUGAGCUUUGGAGCAUCUUAAGGAGCUCAGCUCAGCAAACAACUCUUGCAUUUCAGCCAGAAAGAGCCUCUUGUAACAAAGUAUUCAAAGGGGAGAGUUUCUGCAUCUUUUACUUUGCAGUCCACUAUGGUAGAAAACUUGACAUUCCAUAGAUAAUGAUACUGGGUUUUCUUUCCAAGAUGCCAGCUUUAAAAGAAAUAUGAGCCAUUCUAAGCUUUAAGAAGGGUUCAGGAAACACAGGAAUUAGUAGACAGCCCUCCCAAUGCAGGUUAAGACGACAGCCUGCGCCCCCAACUAGCACAGCUCAGCGAGCAUGACCAUAUGCCAUUCUCGUCUCCAGAGAGCUGGUGGCAGUGACCUCACUAGGAGAAAACACAUCCCUCAGCCGUGGGACUUGACAGAAUGAGGUGCGCGAGGGAGGCCGCUAGCCGAGACUUGGCCUUUCCUGACUGCCCCUGUGUUACCUGGGCAGCUCCAGAUCACUGAGCCCACAAUGGCUGAGAAGGGUGACUGCAUCGCCAGUGUCUAUGGGUAUGACCUCGGUGGGCGCUUUGUUGACUUCCAACCCCUGGGCUUCGGUGUCAAUGGUUUGGUGCUGUCGGCCGUGGACAGCCGGGCCUGCCGGAAGGUCGCUGUGAAGAAGAUUGCCCUGAGCGAUGCCCGCAGCAUGAAGCACGCGCUCCGAGAGAUCAAGAUCAUUCGGCGCCUGGACCACGACAACAUCGUCAAAGUGUACGAGGUGCUCGGUCCCAAGGGCACUGACCUGCAGGGUGAGCUGUUCAAGUUCAGCGUGGCGUACAUCGUCCAGGAGUACAUGGAGACCGACCUGGCACGCCUGCUGGAGCAGGGCACGCUGGCAGAAGAGCAUGCCAAGCUGUUCAUGUACCAGCUGCUCCGCGGGCUCAAGUACAUCCACUCCGCCAACGUGCUGCACAGGGACCUGAAGCCCGCCAACAUCUUCAUCAGCACAGAGGACCUCGUGCUCAAGAUUGGGGAUUUCGGGUUGGCAAGGAUCGUUGAUCAGCAUUACUCCCACAAGGGUUAUCUGUCAGAAGGGUUGGUAACAAAGUGGUACCGUUCCCCACGACUGCUCCUUUCCCCCAAUAACUACACCAAAGCCAUCGACAUGUGGGCCGCCGGCUGCAUCCUGGCUGAGAUGCUUACGGGGAGAAUGCUCUUUGCUGGGGCCCAUGAGCUGGAGCAGAUGCAACUCAUCCUGGAGACCAUCCCUGUAAUCCGGGAGGAAGACAAGGACGAGCUGCUCAGGGUGAUGCCUUCCUUUGUCAGCAGCACCUGGGAGGUGAAGAGGCCUCUGCGCAAGCUGCUCCCUGAAGUGAACAGUGAAGCCAUCGACUUUCUGGAGAAGAUCCUGACCUUUAACCCCAUGGAUCGCCUAACAGCUGAGAUGGGGCUGCAACACCCCUACAUGAGCCCAUACUCGUGCCCUGAGGACGAGCCCACCUCACAACACCCCUUCCGCAUUGAGGAUGAGAUCGACGACAUCGUGCUGAUGGCCGCUAACCAGAGCCAGCUGUCCAACUGGGACACGUGCAGUUCCAGGUACCCUGUGAGCCUGUCGUCGGACCUGGAGUGGCGGCCUGACCGGUGCCAGGACGCCAGCGAGGUACAGCGCGACCCGCGCGCGGGUUCGGCGCCACUGGCUGAGGACGUGCAGGUGGACCCGCGCAAGGACUCGCACAGCAGCUCCGAGCGCUUCCUAGAGCAGUCGCACUCGUCCAUGGAGCGCGCCUUCGAGGCCGACUACGGGCGCUCCUGCGACUACAAGGUGGGGUCGCCGUCCUACCUGGACAAGCUGCUGUGGCGCGACAACAAGCCGCACCACUACUCGGAGCCCAAGCUCAUCCUGGACCUGUCGCACUGGAAGCAGGCGGCCGGCGCGCCCCCCACGGCCACGGGGCUGGCGGACACGGGGGCGCGCGAGGACGAGCCGGCCAGCCUCUUCCUGGAGAUCGCGCAGUGGGUCAAGAGCACGCAGGGCGGCCCAGAGCACGCCAGCCCGCCCGCCGACGACCCCGAGCGCCGCUUGUCUGCCUCGCCCCCCGGCCGCCCGGCCCCGGUGGACGGCGGCGCCAGCCCCCAGUUCGACCUGGACGUGUUCAUCUCCCGCGCCCUGAAGCUCUGCACCAAGCCCGAGGACCUGCCGGACAAUAAACUGGGCGACCUCAAUGGUGCGUGCAUCCCCGAGCACCCUGGCGACCUCGUGCAGACCGAGGCCUUCUCCAAAGAAAGGUGGUGAGGGCGGAGGGGCCGCUCCAGGCCCCACAGAGCAGGAGACCCCCAGAGAAAGCCGGGGCUGGCAGGAGGCGGCCGCCCUUCCCGCCCCUCUCUGCUGCCUUGGGGUUGGCAGAACACGUGAAGGAUCCGAGGAGCGAGAGGAAUGUCCAUUUCUUAAACUGCCUUAAUAACUAGCCUUUAACCUGUGGGAGCGGGUUUGAACAGGACCCUGGCUUAGGGGUUGAUCACUUUCCUAGCAAAGGGGAGACCACAUGUGGUGCACAGGGAAGAAACGGCUUUAGACAGCAGUCUGCGGGCCCCACCUGGGUGGCAGGAUGCCGAGAAAUCUUGCAGAGGUAGCUCCGAAACCAUCUGGCCCAACUAGCCUCAACUGACAGCUGAGGAAAGGCAAUUAGGCCCAGAGAGGCAGAGACACUCGCUUAAGAUCACAGGCUUAGUGUGAGGACGAGCUUGAAAUCCCAGUCUCCUGGCCCCCAGGCCAGGGUCUGUCCACCAUAGAAUGUCUUCCUCUACUGGGGUCGUUCUGGCUUUUUGUUAGAAACUUGGUCUGAGAUGUUUCUUCCCUGUCCAUUACCAUUCGAUGUUCUUUUAUUCAGAGCAAUGUUUCUUGUAUUCUGAAACUGGAAACUGAACCAGUUUGUUUCUCCUAGUCACCAAGCAUACUUUCCUGGCUCCCCAAGUACUUAAAUGUUCUCAUCUGUCGCACCCCUGUAUUUGCCUCACCCCUGCAUGGUCGGAAAUCUUCGUUUCAGGUCAGAACAGCCUGGGGUCUGUGGGUAAAAUCAGCCCUUCUCCCAGGCCUGUGCACACACCCCCUCAGCACUCCCUAUGCACUUUCCUGACACGCAAAGACACAGCCCUCUUUCCCCACUGGGCGUCCUACCCCAGUGAGGUUGAAGGCACCAAUUCCAAGAAUCCCUCCAACCUCCCUGCCAGCACUCCCCCUUCACCCCACACCCGGCCCCCCCACCUAACCACAGCGCCUCUCCAGACCUACCUCGGGACCUAAUGUUCUCUACAUGAACUGCUCAUUUGGAGGACAGCAGUGAGGUCCUGCCAUAGAGCAAAUGUGUUAGGAGAGAAGGUUUCACAUGGGACCCAACAUCCUUCAUCAAUACUUUCCUGAGUUUGAUCAUCCAUUUAGCCUUGACAAACAGCAGACCCUACAGAGAUGUGUUGGAGAGCACGUCGUGACCUUGGGGGCAAGGAAUCCAGAAAGGUAGGAAGAUAUGAAAAGAGAGGUGUCAACAGCAAGGGCUCUUAGGGGUCAGGCACCAGCAUGGAGACCUCAUGACAAAGGAAGGGACUCAAAGCAGCAAUGCCCCUCAUAGUGUAGGCUAAGGUGAGUUUGGUGCAUGCAAACCUGUGUGCUCACCCACAGAGCAUGGGGUAAUGGUGUGUAGACACAGGCCCUCUGCAGAAGCGUGGGGUGGGGACACUGACAGCCCCUAUCUGGUCCCCAGGAACAUUCUACCAUUUCUGCCACUGGUGUUCAGCUCCUUCUCUUCCCCCAACACUCCCAAAGAUACCCACAGGAAGUCCAGCCAGUUUCCAGGUAGAGGAUUCCACCAGUUGGUCUUGGGCUGCGUUCACCCUCACAUCACAGCACCUUAAAUCUAAUCAGCAAACUAUAAUUUGUACGUUGAAACCUGCAACACAUUAGAAACUUAUAUUUAAAAACAGAAUUAAUCACACUGACCAACUUUUAAAUGGAAAAUAUGUAAAUAGGAAGUGUUUGGGUUUUGUUUUUUCUUUAAGAAAAAGAAAUGUACACCACUCCUCAUGUGCCAUUUUGUCCUCAGAGGGCGGCUUUACUUUUUUGGUAAAGGAACAAGCUGCUGGCCUUGACCAGGAGUUCAUAUAUAACUGUUAUUACAGAGGAAUUGUUAUAACUACUAAUGUUUUUAAAAAAUUUAUUAAACAUUAUUAAACUUGAUCAGGUCAGGCCAAAUAAAGUUUUAUUGGAACACAGA